GCAGAGGGCUGGACUCAGCGGCGGAGCUGGCUGCUGGCCUCAGUUCUGCCUCUGUCCAGGUCCUUGUGACCCGCCCGCUCUCCUAAGGGAGCGUGUCCUGGCCCCCUCCCGCAGCGGCUCGGAAAAAAGGCAGCACCGCGUCGUUGACGGCGCGGGCUCUGGACUCGCUGCUUGGUAAAAACCUUCCUCUUCCUCCAGUGCGGGACGCACUCUCUGGUAUCUCUUUUGACCUCCCGGAGGCUUUCCUUUGUCGGUCGCGGCGCCACUGUACUAUGGCAUACCUCGUUUUAUUACGCUUCGCAGAUAGGGCAUUCUGAAAACAAAUGGAGGGUUUGUGGCAGCCCUGAGUCCAGCAAUUGUAUCAGCGCCAUUUUUCCAACAGCAUGUGCUCACUUGGUGUCUCUGUGUUACAUUUUGGUAAUUCUCAAAAUAUUUAAAACUUUUUCAUGAUUUCUGUGUCUGUUAUGGUGAUCUAUGAUCAGUGAUCUUUGAUGUUGCUAUUGUCAUUGUUUUGGGGUGCCACAUACAGCGUCUUUUAUAAGACGUGGAACUUAAUGUUGUGUGUGUUCUGACCGCUCCACCCACAGACCGUUCCCCAUCUCUCUCCCUCUUCUUGGGCCUCCCUAUUCCCUGAGACACAACAAUAUUGAGAUUAGGCGAAUUAAUGACUCUGCAAUGGCCUCUAAGUGCUCAAGUGAAAGGAAGAGUCGCACAUCUCUCACUUUAAAUCAAAAACUAGAAAUGAUUAAACUGAGUGAGGAAGGUAUGUCAAAAGCCGAGAUAGGCCGAAGGCUAGGCCUCCUGCGGCAAACAGUUAGCCAAGUUGUAAAUGCAAAGGAAAAGUUCUUGAAGGAAGUUAAAAGUGCUACUCCAAUGAACACACGAAUGAUAAGAAAGCGAAACAGCCUUAUUGCUGAUAUGGAGAAGGUUUUAGUGGUCUGGAUAGAAGAUCAGACCAGCCGCAACAUUCCCUUAAGCCAAAGCCUAAUCCAGAACAAAGCCCUAACUCUCUUCAACUCUAUGAAAGCUGAGAGAGGUGUGGAAGCUGCAGAAGAAAAGUUUGAAGCUAGCAGAGGUUGGUUCAUGAGGUUUAAGGAAAGAAGCCAUUUCCAUAACAUAAAAGCACAAGGUGAAGCAGCAAGUGCUGAUGUAGAAGCUGCAGCAAGUUAUCCAGAAGCUUUAGCUAAGAUCAUUGACGAAGGUGGCUACACUAAACAACAGAUUUUCAAUGUAGAUGAAACAGCCUUCUAUUGGAAGAAGAUGCCAUCUAGAACUUUCAUAGCUAGAGAGGAGAAGUCAGUGCCUGGCUUCAAAGCUUCAAAGGACAGGCUGACUCUCUUGUUAGGGGCUAAUGCAGCUGGUGACUUUAAGUUGAAGCCAAUGCUUAUUUACCAUUCUGAAAAUCCUAGGGCCCUUAAGAAUUAUACUAAAUCUACUCUACCCGUGCUAUAUAAAUGGAACAGCAAAGCCCGGAUGACAGCACAUCUGUUUACAGCGUGGUUUACUGAAUAUUUUAAACCCACUGUUGAGACCUACUGCUCAGAAAAGAAGAUUCCUUUCAAAAUAUUACUGCUCAUUGACAAUGCCCCUAGUCAUCCAAGAGCUCUGAUGGAGAUAUACGAGGAGAUUAAUGUUAUUUUCAUGCCUGCUAACACAACAUCCAUUCUGCAGCCCAUGGAUCAAGGGGUAAUUUCGACCUUCAAGUCUUAUUAUUUGAGAAAUACAUUUCAUAAGGCUCUAGCUGCCAUGGAUAGUGAUGUCUCUGAUGGAUCUGGGCAAAGCAAAUUGAAAACCUUCUGGAAAGGAUUCACCAUUUUAGAUGCCAUUAAAAACAUUCGUGAUUCAUGGGAGGAGGUCAAAUUGUCAACAUUAACAGGAGUUUGGAAGAAGUUGAUUCCCACCCUCAUUGAUGACUAUGAGGGGUUCAAGACUUCAGUGGAGGAAGUAAGUGCAGAUGUGGUGGAAAUAGCAAAAGAACUAGAAUUAGAAGUAGAGCCUGAAGAUGUAACUGAAUUGCUGCAAUCUCAUGAUAAAACUUUAACAGAUGAGGAGUUGUUUCUUAUGGAUGCGCAAAGAAAGUGGUUUCUUGAGAUGGAAUCUACACCUGGUGAAGAUGCUGUGAACAUUGUUGAAAUGACAACAAAGGAUUUAGAAUAUUACAUAAACUUAGUUGAUAAAGCAGCAGCAGGGUUUGAGAGGAUUGACUCCAAUUUUGAAAGAAGCUCUACUGUGGGCAAAAUGCUAUCAAACAGCAUCGCAUGCUACAGAGAAAUCUUUCAUGAAAGGAAGAGUCAACUCAUGCGAAAAGCUUCACCGAUGUCUUAUUUUAGGAAAUUGCCACAGCCACCCCAACCUUCAGCAGCCACCACCCUGACCAGUCAGCAACCAUCAACCUCGAGGCAAGACCCUCCACCAGCAAAAAGAGUACGACUCACCGAAGGCUCAGAUUGAUAAUCAGCAUUUUUUAGCAAUAAAGUAUUUUUAAAUUUAGGUAUGUAUAUUGUUUUAUUAGACAAUGCUAUUGCACUCUUGCUGGUCUACAGUAUAGUGUAAACAUAACUUUUAUAUGCAUUGGGAAACCAAAAACAUUCAUGUGACUUGCUUUCUUGUGUUGGUCUGGAACUGAACCUGCAAUGUCUUUGAGGUAUGCCUCGACCUACCUCCUUAGGUUGCUGUAUGGAUCCCAUGAGACAGUAACUUAUAGUAAUGGCAGCUAAUGUUAACAUUUGAGUGUUUAUUGUGUACAAGGAGCUAAUCCUCUGCCCUCUGAGGCUUUCAGAGAGGUUGAGAGACUUGUGCCAGAUACACAACUAGUAAGGGGCUGGUGGGAACCGGAAAUGGCCCCACUGUCAUCAGAUUCCCUCCCUGAUUGAAGUUCUCCCCCACUCUCCCUAACUCCUCUAGUUCUCUAUAGCUCUGACUCUGCUCUUGCUUCAAACACACUGUGCAUGCACAGACACAGACUCACACUGGAGUAAAUAAUACGAACUUGCUGGUGAUUGAAUCCCAAAGACAGCAAUCCUGUGCUUGGAGGGAGGGCAUAUUUCCAAGGUCCCCUCCUGCCAGCAUAUCCUGUCGUCAGGCCUUUAUGUGGCACUUUCACUUUUCUUUUUUCAGUUUUGUAAUUUUUUUAUUUUUUUUGAGACAGGGUCUUACUGUGUCAUCAGGCUGGAGUGCAGUCACAUGAUCACAGCUCACUGCAGCCUAGACCUCCUGGGCUCAAGCGAUCCUCCCACCUCAGCCUCCCGAGUAACUGGGACUACAGGCAUGCAUCACCACGCCCAGCUAAGUUUUGUAUUUUUUGGUAGAGGCCGGGUGUCCCCAUGUUGCCCAGGCUGGGUUCCUGGGUUCGUGGGCUCCUGAGCUCAAGCAGUCCACCCACCUUGUCCUCCCAAGGUGCUGGGAUUGCAGGUGUGAGCCACCACACCUGGCCAGGAAUGGAUUAUUUUUUGCACCUUAUUUACAGAUGAGGGAACAGCCUCAGGGAGCAUAGGUGACUUGCCCAAGGGUGUCCCCUGGUUACCAGCCAAACUCGUGUGCCGGCUGUAAUCUCAGAGCAGGACCUUGCCUCUCCCCCAGGAAGACCCCAGCCUUACUACCUGAUUAGUGGGGUCAAGGGAGGCCAGUCAAAGUCUCCUCCUGGAAUGAAGAGCUCAGUGGCUCUCUGUUAACUCCACACCUCCUCUUGCCUAGCUCUUCCUUGUCUUAACCAUCCUUUGGGAAGAAGGGCCUGUUUUUCAGGCCGUAGAAUCUUAGAGUGUCAGAUUGGGUCAGAGUCAGGAAUUCUGGACUUCAAACCUUGUUUAACCACCACUGUUGUGUGGAGUCCCGCUUACUCUAGGCUCAAUUUGCCUAUAUAACAUGGGGAAUAAUGACUCUUGCUUAUCCAUACUGCUGUGAGGAGCUCUUAAUUAAAAAGGAGGCCAGGUACAGUGGCUUAUGCCUGUAAUCCCAAGACUCAAGUGGGAGGAUCACUUGAGCUCAGGAGUUCAAGACCAACCUAGGCAACAUAGCAAAACCUCAUCUCUACUAAAAAUUUAAAAGUAGCUGGGUGUAGUGGUGCAUGCCUGUGGUGCCAGCUACUUGGGAGGCUGAGGCAGGAGCAUUGCUUGAGCCCUGGAGGUUGAGGCUGCAGUGAGCCAUGAUCAUGCCACUCCACUCCAACUUGCAUGACAAGAGUGAGGCUCUAUCUCAAAACUAAACAAAACAACAACAACACAUCAAAAACUAAAAAAAAAAAAAAAAAAAAGAGGAUUACAAAACUCAGGAAAUCGUCUUGUGGUCAGUGGCAGAAAAAUGCACAUGAAUGGAAAGGCCACUGGGGCUGUUGAGAAUUGGGUGCUUAUUGUACCCAGAAGGCACGGGGGGGAGAUGCCAGCUGGUAUGGGCUGCUGCCCUGCUUUGGAGAGAGCAUCGGCUGCUACUCUUCACACCUCUUGUGACUGCCCUCUUUCAGGGAGAACUUGUAAAAGGGGAGCCAGUCCCAAGUCCGAAGGUAUUAUACAAAACAGUCCUUCGGGCUUCAGACUGAUGGGAAUGAAUAAUGCUUUGCCUAAGUGAGGGGAGUGCACUGAGUGGAGGGGUGGCUGGUGCCAGGAUGAGCUAGCCAAUCCCACGUGUGUGCUGACUGCAGCAGGACACUAGCCACGGCCCACCCCCAACCACUCUCGGACUCCAGCUCAGACUGUUUCCCCAGCUUUUCUCAGGGCUGUUUGGCUCACACAGUCCUGAAGGGCACUUCCCAAAGAGCACACUUAGGACCUCAGUAGGAGAACGUGGCUGAUAAGACUCAGUGUGACCCACGUGUGUGACUCCCACAUGCCCCACAGUGGUUGGUUGGCUCAGUCUGGUGAGGGCAGGUAGGGGCGUGGAUCUCCAGGGAAUGGCAGGGCCGGCACCCGGUUGUAGUGGGCCAUGAGGAAGAUGCCAGCUGUGCCACAGAUGAAGAGCGAGAGCAUGGCCAGGAAGCAGACGCGGUCCAGCACUCGGCCCACCAGGAACCACUCCUCAUUCCCCUGAGGGUGGGAGGCAGGUGUGGGAUAACCAGCGGCGGCACCAGGUCUUCCCUGGGUCCUGUUCUCAUCCUUGGGCUUCCAGCAGGCCCAUGUCUCCAUUUCCUGGGGCCCUUCUUACCUAUGUCCGGGUCCCAACUGGUGGCUAAUUCCAUGGCCCCCUGGCCCUGAGGUGCCCCCCCUGCCCCUGUUCCUUUUUCUUUCUUUCUUUCCUUUUUUUUUUUUUUGAGACGGAGUCUCACGUCUCACUCUUUCACCCAGGCCAGAGUGCAGUGGUGCGAUCUUGGCUUGGCUCACUGCAACCUCCGCCUCCCAGGUUCAAGCAAUUCUCCUGCCUCAGCCUCCUGAGUAGCUGGGAAUACAGGUGCCCGCCACCACACCCAGCUAAUUUUUGGUAUUUUUGGUAUUUUUGGUAGAGAUAGGGUUUUGCCAUGUUGGCCAGGCUGGUCUCAAACUCCUGACCUCAGGUGAUCCACUCGCCUCGGCCUCCCAAAGUACUGGGAUUACAGGUGUGACCCACUGCACCCGGCCUCAUGUUUUUCCAUCCCACUGCCCUAUCUUGGCAACCCCACUCAUCCUGUCUCUAUCACGGUUCCAAGCCCAGGUACUCACUCCACCUCCACCCCACCCUGACUCAGCUUACAUUGUCAAAGUGACUCUGCUGGUGCCGGGCACAGGCAAUGAGGUUGCAGGCUUCCACACAGGCCUGGAUGGCUGGGGCAGCCUGCUUCAGGCUGCCACAGAACUGGCUCAGCCCUAACUCCGGGCCUUUCUCUGAUAAAGAGAAAGGGUAAGGUUUGGGAGUAGAAUGGAGGAGAAACAGGCAGAGAAGAUGGCCUCUCCUUAGGGACCCCAGCUCCUCUCUCCCUGACCUGGGCACUUCUCCAGCACUCAUCUGCUGUGCCUGGCUCCCCAGCUGGGGUCCCAGGGGAGGACUGUCCCCAGGCACACCUGGUGUGUCUCACCUAGCUUCUCCAGCGCUGCCGCCACCAGCCCUUGCCGCUGCCACUGCUGGAAGAGGAGUUCACUGCGAGGCAGGCAGAGGGCCACCUCCUCCCCAGUUGUGAUCGACCAUCCCGAGGAGCCAUUCUGUAGCCGGGACUGGGUGUCCUGCACAGCUGCCGGGGCCAGCGGGCGAACGUGCAUCCUCAGCAGCUGGGGCAAGAGCCUCAGGAACACCUAGAGAGGGGGUGGCUUCACUAGGGCAGCAGGCCGAGCUUCAGAGCAGAAGCCAGAGGUUGGCGUGAAGGGCUUGUGCUGCUAGGGACCAUGGAGGCAGCAUACCGGGGCAGUGACGUGGCCUUGGUAAAGCUUUCUAUACUGGACACGAGCCUGGGUCCCCAAACUUCAGUGCACAUCAGAAUCACCAGGGCACUUGUUAUAAACACAGAUUCCUGCCCCCAGCCCUCAUGCUAUUCUGGCCUAGAAUGCCUGGGACAGGCCUGGGAAUCUGCAUGUGCAACAAGGGCCCAAGCUGAAGGCUGCAGGUGGGCUACAGAUCACACAGACUGGAAUCAGACUGCCCUGGCAGACUCCUGCUUUUUCGACUUUGUAGUGCACUUCCUUGGGCAGGUUACUUAACCUCUCUGCGCCUCAACGUCCUCAUCUGUAAUUGGAGGUGAUAUGGGUUUUAUGAAGAUGAAAUACAUUAACAUUUGUAAUA